ACGCCGACGUCAAGUCGAGGCCGCCGCCGCGGGGCCUGGUUAUCGCCGGUUCAGCGCAGCCCGGAGUCGCCCAGGCCUGAACUCCUACCCAGGUCCCCGGCCCCCGCCCCGGGCCCGCGAGGACACCGGAGGCCACCCCCCGGGGGUGGGGAGCGGAGCCGCGGGCCAGCUCUGCGAGCGCCCCGCGCUGGCCUGUCCGGCCCCGCCCCCGCCCCGGGCCAUGGCCCAGCCCUUGUCCCGGCCCCUCGUCCUAUCCCAAUCCCCGCCUUGGCCCCCAGCCCCGCCCUCGCCCCGCUUCCCACAUCGGCCCCAGCCCCUGCCUGGGUCCCCAUCCAGGACCCCCUUCCAGUCUCUGCCCCUGGCCUGGCCCCCAUCCCGGCCUCGGCCCUCGUUCCACCCCCUGUCACAAAUCCCAGCCCAGGCCCUGUCCCAGCCCCAUUCCCAGUGUUUGCUUAAGGCCCUGGCUCAACCCCGUCCCUUGCUGCAGUCCCCAUCACAGCCCUUCCUUCCAUCCCACUCCCUGCCCUUGUUCAAGCCCCAGUGUCCAGCCCAGCCCAACCCAUUAUCUCAGCCUUUGCCCUCAUCUCUGUGUUUACCCAAGUCUCUCCCUCUAGUCCCCCCUAUCUCUCAUACUCUGCCCCUCUCCCAGCCUAGACUCAAGUCUGGGUUUCAGCUGCCGCCAGCCCUAUUGCUGCUGUUGCUGUUCUCUGUCCUUGGCCCAGGGGCUGGAGGCCUUUUCCUGACUGAUUACUCCACCUGCUCACCCCGCAAGCUGAGUCCUUUCCGCUCCUUUGCCAGCACCGAGCUCUUCCACUUCCAUGUUCCUGAGGACACAUUCCUGGCUGUUUGGAACCUCAUCAUCUUCAAGGAGCAAGGGGGAACUUUUGGGGACCACUGCCCAGACCAAAGUGUGACUGUGUAUUUCCGGUCCGGGGCACCCCCUGUCAUCAAUCCCCUGCAUACACACUUCCCAGGGGACACAGCUGUGCCUGGGGUUUUCUCACUGACCCUCAGCUGGACACUGCCCAACCGCACCUCAGGCAUCUUUAACGUCAGCAGCCCCUUACCUGGGGACUGGUUCUUGGCUGCCCACCUUCCCCAGGCCCACGGCCACAUCUCUGUCAAGGGUCUCCAGGAUGAGUGUCAGUACCUCCUUCAGCCGCAGCUGAUUGUCCGGCGUUUGCUGGACGUCGCUGUGCUGGUUCCUGGCCGGCCCUCAGAGCAAACCCUCUCCCCACACAAUCGCUCAGCCCUGUACAAGGUCUUUGUGCCCAGCUUCACUUACAGGGUUUCAGCACAGCUGGUGUGUGUGGGGGGCCGUGGGGUAUCUGCCUGCCCCCUGUCACUGCGUCUGCGUCCCAAAGCCCCACCCCUGCACAACUCAAGCUCUGUGGCCUGUGGAGGUGCCUCAGGAUGCCAGCUGGAGCUGGCACUGCCCCCCUGGGGGCACUGGGUCUACGUGCGUGUGGAAACAUCAUCCCGGGGCCCUGGUAGGACCAUCCGCUUCCAGCUGUGUGUGCGGUUGCAAGAGUGCCCACAGCCCGGCCUGCUCCGAGCCCUGGUCCCUGGAGCUGCCAUGAACAUGCCCCAGUCCCUGGGCAACCAGCCACUGCCCCCAGAACCGCCAUCCCUUGGAACCCCUGCGGAGGGGCCUGGGACCACGUCCCCACCCGAGCACUGCUGGCCAGUGCGCCCGACUCUGCGCAACGAGCUGGACACCUUCUCUGUCCACUUCUACAUCUUCUUUGGCCCAAGUGUGGCCCUUCCCCCUGAGCGCCCAGCCGUGUUCGCCAUGAGGCUGUUGCCAGUGCUGGACAGUGGAGGCGUCCUCAGCCUGGAGCUCCAGCUCAAUGCGUUUUUCUGUUCUGAGAAUGGAGGUGAGAGAGCAGCUUUGGCGUGGAGAGCGCCGGGAGGAAUGGGCUGUCCUUGGAAGAGCUCCGUGCGCCAGGAAAACGUGACGGUGUUUGGAUGCUUGACUCACGAGGUGCCCUUGAGCCUGGGGGAUGCAGCAGUGACCUGUUCCAAAGAGUCCCUGGCCGGCUUCCUCCUCUCUGUCAGUGCCACCACCAGGGUUGCCAGGCUGCGAAUCCCAUUCCCGCAGACGGGGACCUGGUUCCUGGCCCUCCGCUCCCUGUGCGGGGUGGGGCCUCGGUUCGUGCGGUGCCGCAACGCGACGGCCGAGGUGCGGAUGCGCACCUUCCUGUCCCCAUGCGUGGACGACUGCGGGCCCUACGGCCAGUGCAAGCUGCUGCGCACACACAAUUAUCUGUACGCAGCCUGCGAGUGCAAGGCCGGGUGGAGAGGCUGGGGCUGCACCGACAGUGCAGAUGCGCUCACCUAUGGAUUCCAGCUGCUGUCCACACUCCUGCUCUGCCUGAGCAACCUCAUGUUUCUGCCACCUGUGGUCCUGGCCAUUCGGAGUCGAUAUGUGCUGGAAGCUGCAGUCUACACCUUCACCAUGUUCUUCUCCACGUUCUAUCAUGCCUGUGACCAGCCAGGCAUCGUGGUUUUCUGCAUCAUGGACUACGAUGUGCUGCAGUUCUGUGAUUUCCUGGGCUCCUUAAUGUCCGUGUGGGUCACUGUCAUUGCCAUGGCUCGUUUACAGCCCGUGGUCAAGCAGGUGCUGUAUUUGCUGGGAGCUAUGCUGCUGUCCAUGGCUCUGCAGCUUGACCGACAUGGACUCUGGAACCUGCUUGGACCCAGUCUCUUCGCCCUGGGGAUCUUGGCCACAGCCUGGACAGUACGCAGCGUCCGCCGCCGGCACUGCUACCCACCCACGUGGCGCCGCUGGCUUUUCUACUUGUGCCCUGGCAGCCUUAUUGCAGGCAGUGCCGUCCUGCUUUAUGCUUUUGUGGAGACCCGGGACAACUACUUCUACAUUCACAGCAUUUGGCAUAUGCUCAUUGCGGGCAGUGUGGGCUUCCUGCUGCCCCCUCGUGCCAAGACUGACCACGGGGUCCCAUCUGGAGCCCGGGCCCGGGGCUGUGGUUACCAGCUAUGCAUCAACGAGCAGGAGGAGCUGGGCCUCGUGGGCCCAGGAGGGGCCACUGUCAGCAGCAUCUGUGCCAGCUGAGAGGGGCUUUGGGCCUGGCCCUGAGGGGAUAUGAAUGCUUCCUAGAGUUCUUUCUGGGGGUGUGGAGCCCUCUUAGAAGGAGACAGGCUGUAUUUCUUGAGGACAUGGAGUCUUUCUCAAGGACACAAAACUCUUCCAGGGACCUGGAGCCCUUCCCAGGACAUGGAGAACUUCCUGAGGGCCUGGAGUCCCCCUGCAUCAUGGAGUCCUUCUUAAGGACUGGAGCCUAUGCAGGCACAGAGUCCCUCAGGACCAAGGAGUCCCUCCUGCAGGUGUGGAGCCUUUCCUGGGAUGCAGAGCCUUCCCAAGACAUGGAUUCCUUCCCAGGGAGACAAAGCCCUGUCAGGAGCACAGCAUCUUUCCAGAGGAGGUGGAGUCUAUCUUGGGGAAACCAAAUUUCCAGAUUUUCCCAGAGGCUCAGCAACUCUGGCCUCAGGCUUCCUUCCCAGAGGCAGCGUCUGGGCUGUGCUGUGCUGUGGAGGAGGGAUUGCAGGAUGGAUGGAGCUGGGACUGGGGCUGUCUGGGUGGCUGGUAUCCUCGUUUGAUACAGGUGGAGUCUGUGUGUCUCCAGUGAUUGAUUGGUUCAGAAUGGUUCUGUGAUGCCUUUUUUCCCCCUGGGGUCAGGGGUGUGGGGAAGUGGGGAAAGAGGGCCCCUCAGGGAAUCAGCAGGGCUGAUGGGAGCUACUGCCGGAGGCUUUUGUCACACCCUGUACACAGUCUGAUCCCGCUCAUCUGGGCCCUGCAUUCAUUUCUAAACAGUUUCUAAUGCCUAUUCCCCAAUUCCUAUUGAGCCCGAUUUGCAGUAUCUGAGGGGUGUGUGUGUGUGUGUGUGUGUUUAUGUAUGUAUACGUAUGCUGAGAUGAUUUAAAUCAGUGAGACAGACUUUCCUUAUGAUGCCCACACCCAACACAGAAGGAAGCCGAGGUCCCAGGAAAUUGGAAUAGCAGGUACACGUCUCAGGUGUGCAAGAAAUAUCACAAGAAUGUAACUUCUGUUUUGAGCCCCCAUUUUUCCUGAGUGCCAGAAAAGAUCAUUUGUCCAUUUGGGAUUCCUUCUCUUUCCAUGAGGGUCAUAGCUGAGUUCUGAGGGUCUUACAUAAUGCCAAGAAGUUGGGAGAGCAUUCUCACUGAUCACCAGUGUCCAUACUUCAUCCAUCCCCGGGAUUUCCAUCAUUCCAUCUGGUCCCCAGUCAGAGGUCCAGACAGUUCAUCUGGGAUGCAGAGAGAUUUCUUGUUCCCAUUUGCAUUACUCUCUCAGUCCUAAGGUUCUCUCUGCCACUUCUGGGCCAUAUGUGGAGACCCGUAAAGUUGUCUAAGGCCUUGGCUAUGCAGACACACCUUGAAGCUGUUUCUGCUCUGGGUUUUGACAGACAAGGCAUGAGUUGCUGCAUCUGUUAAAACUGCAAAUCUAUCUUGGCCUGGGGUGUGGAGCUCAGGGACUCUUCCUUUUGGGACCCUCUGUGUCAGUAUUCUCACUACAUCCUCUCCUCCUCUCUCUUCUUUCCCCCUUUCGUUAAUAUUGGAGGUGAGGAAGCCUUACUUAAUGUUUUCUCCUGAAUCUUUUUUUUUUUGAGACGGAGUUUUGCUCUUGUUGCCCAGGCUGGAAUGCAAUGGUGCGAUCUCAGCUCACUGCAACCUCUGCCUCCCGGGUUCAAGUGAUUCUCCUGUCUCAGCCUCCCGAGUAGCUGGGAUUAGAGGUGUGCACCACCAAGCCCAGCUAAUUUUUGUAUUUUUAGUAGAGAUGGGGUUUCUCCAUGUUGGUCAGGCUGCUCUCAAACUCCCGGCCUCAGGUGAUCCACCCGCCUCGGCCUCCCAAAGUGCUGGGAUUACAGUUGUGAGCCACCGCGCCUGGCCUCUCCUGAAUCUUUUAUCUAUGCCUUAAGCCUUUUCUGUUCCCUUCAGGACCUAGGCUUUUGAAACCCAAAAGCCAGGAAAACAUGCCUUUGUUAUCUGCUUUCUGCAAUCACGUCUCUUCCAUGGGGCACUGAGCAGAGAAUGGUGUGGCCAAGUGAGUAGUGAGAAGCAGUGAGGAGGUGUGAGCUAGGUGUCUGUUCCCAUUUUAGAAAAUACUGUUCCUACAUCAGAAAUACCACAUUAAGACGUAUAGAGCCAGGUCACUGGGAUGCUUGAACCCAAAUAGCUGGGAUUCUGGACAGAGUCAGCAGAGUACAGAAGGCUCUGAAGUGGGAGACGGAGCUGGGGUGCAUCCCUCCCAGUGAGGAGGGGUCAUGAGGGGCGUCUGGGAAGAGGGACAUUUGAACUAGGAUUAGCUGAGUUGCCAUGAUGCUAAGAUAAUGGGAGAGUGUUCUUUGUGGUCACCAGUGUCCACAUGGCAUCCCUUCCCUGAGAUUUUCAUCACUCCCUGUGGUCUUCAGUCAGUAAAGCUCUUAGAACACUUGUAUAGUGCCUAGUCUGGUAUGUGAUGUGGUCCAAUAUAUGUUAGCUUAAGGUCACCACGUGUUUGGACAUGGAGAGGGAACAGCAAGGGGGAAUGCAGAGGCAGGAAAGACUGAUAUUUACUCCGGGCACUGAAUAGUUCAGUGUGCCUGGGCCAGUGCAUGUGCGCAUGCUUUUGUGUGUGGAGUGGGGUGGUGGAGGUAAGCAGCCAAUGAUAUGAUUAGAUAGAUAAGUGGAGGUUGGGUCUUUAUUCUAUGGGAAAUGAGGAGCCAUUGGAGAGAUUAAGCAGGAGAGGAACAUCAGAUUGGGGUUUUGAUGGCUGGGGCAGAGGAUGGACUUUGGGAGACCUUGGAGGACAAAGUGCAGUGACCACAGCUAUUGGAACAUUUGAAAGAGAAAUGGUGAAGCCUUCUUAAAGCAAUAUCGGUGGAAAGGAGGGGACCAAUUUAAGAGCUGUUAGGAGUGAACUCUUUAGGACUUGGUGACUGAUUGGGUGUGUGGGGUGGUGAGGUAUGAGAGAGCCUAGGAUGAUGGUGAUAUUCUGAUUUGGGGAUGGUGGUGCCAUUCCCUGAGAUGGUGACACCACUUUGGGUGGGGGGAAGAUGAGCUCCACUUUGGACAGUUUGAGGUGCAUGUGGGAUUCCCGGAGGGAAGGGGGCCAGCAAUAUGACAGUGCUGGACGUAGCCGCUGAACCAGGCCUGUCUCCAGGCUCCCAAAAUGGGAAUCCUUGGUUGUCUCCUGACUUGUCUCAGUGGGGGAGAUCCCAAGAUUCAAACAGCCCUUCCUUGCCUUGAAUACAGGGCUGUGGCUGGCAGAUAUUGCUGUACCCUUGCAUGUAUCUGUACAUACGACUGGACUGAGACCCCUGAGCACUUGCAGCUGCCUGGGGCAUGUUCAGCAGCACAGGGCUCAAUCCCCACAGGGUGAUGUUCUGAAAGCUUCUGAGUGACAAUUCAGUCCCGCAAACCUUCCAUAGGGAACAUGCUGUGGGAGCUACAGAGAUGAGCCAGACCCGACUGAAUCCUGCCCUGAAGGAGCUCACACGGUGGUGAAGUGUCAUGAAUGCAAGUUAGAUGGGACAAGUGUGAAGUGGAAGAUCCUGACAAAGUGCUGUAGGAUGUAAAGAGAGCGAUCUCAAAGUGCAAUGGGAAAGGAUGCAUGAGAGAGAUGGUGUCUAACCUAGCUUUGAAAACUAGUCCCAGCUAUUAUCAGAGAACAGCACAAUACAUACAAGGGUGCGAAGACAUGGGGGUGCGGCAGUACAGAUAAUGUAGCGAGGGGACAGCCAUGUGAAGGGCAUAGUGGAAAAUCAGGCUGAAGAAGCAGGUGGGGGCAGAUUCUGGAGGGCCUUGAGGAUUCAACUGAAGAAUUUGGACUUAAUGGUAAUGGGAGCUGUCAAAAGUCCUUGAUCAGAAGAGUGAUGAAUCAAUCCAGGUUUGACCAAAGUAACAGAACCACUAUGAGUGAUAAAAAGAUUAGACCUUUACAGUCAUGGGAGCAGUUGGAGAAAUCUGUGCAAAACUGUUACUUCUGCAUUUGGUGUUGGGCCUGAAGCUGUUACAGCUCAGCUGGGCCAGCAGUUAGGAAAGAAGGCUGAGUGUGAAGUGAGGGGCAGUAAGGGCACACUAGAAUCCAGAAGGACAAACUGGAACCUGUGCCUGGCUCUUAUGCCUUCAAUCUCAGUGACUGGUGACCUGCAGGAGAAGCUGUCACCUUUGCCAUGGAGCUUGCACUUGGCCCAGCACUCAGCACAGUGGAAGGAGGUGACCUGGUGGGGACUGGACAGGCUGUGCUAAUGGGGAGCCAGCAGAUGAGCAACAUGGGGGUGCCCUCACUGUGUCUGGUGCUGUUCCAUUUUUUUUCUUUCUUUCUUUUUUUUUUUUUUGAGACGGAGUCUCACUCUGUUGCCCAGGCUGGAGUGCAGUGGCGCCAUCUCAGCUCACUGCAGCCUCCACCUCCCAAGUUCAAGCGAUCCUCCCUAGUAGCUGGGAUUACAGGUGCACCACCACACCUGGCUAAUUUUUUGUGUUUUUAGUAGAGGCAGGGUUUCAUCACAUUUCCCGGGCUGGUCUCGAACUCCUGGCCUCAGGUGAUCCUCCCACCUCGGUCUCCCAAAGUGCUGGGAUUACAGGUAUGAGCCACCACACCUGGCCCACUUUUGCCUUCCAAAUCACAUGCAAACUUCUCUGUGGCCAACCCUAACCCACACCCUCUAACCUAGUUUGGUUGACUCAGUAUAAAGCUACCACACGUGAGCUAACCAGAGCUUUCUUGGGACGAUUAACUUGGCAGCAGCCCGUGAAGGAUAGAUGGUCAGGAUAAAGAAAGCCAAACCUCCCAUAGCUCUUGGGUUGACACUGUCAGCUGGUGUGGUAGUCAUUAGGCCAUUCACAAAUCUCUCUGUCCCUCUCGUUUGCCAUCCAGACACACGAUAGUGUGCUUUUCCCCCUUAACAAUAGGUGUGGUCCUGUGCCUUCCUGUUGCCAUUGUGUUGGCCACUGAAAUGUAGGUGGAGGCAACACAGCCACUUCUGAGUAGAAGCUUUAAGAGUCAGUGUAGGCUUUGUUACUUUCCCUUUUCUUUUUGUCAUGGUGACCAGCAGUGUUCCCAAUGGUAGCUGUUUUGUCAUCCUGAGUCCCAGAGGGGUGAAGACCAUGAUGCGGAGCAGAAGCCCCACCAGCCUCUGGUGGACCUGCAUCAGGAGCAAGAAACAAACCUUAAUGGCUUUAAGCCUCUCAAGGUUUGAGGUCAUGACCACAGCACAACCUAGCCUAUGCCAGCUGACAGGGGCAGAGGGCAGCAGUAGCAGUGGGAUGCUUUCCUGGAGAGCAAACCUCCUCUCAGCAGAGUUAGGACGGCAGCUUUCACCUCUGCAUUCCUCAGGCUGUAAAUGAUGGGGUUCAGCGAGGGCGUCACAACCCCGUAGAACAAUGCGACAGUCUUAUCCACGUUGGGAUCCUUGGCCUUGGGUUUGAAGUACAUGAAGGAGAUUGUCCCAUAAAAAACCACCACCACUGUGCGGUGGGCUGAGCAGGUGGAGAAGGCUUUGCACCGGCCUGCAGCAGAGGGUACCCUAAGGAUGGCAGACAGGAUGAAAAGGUAAGACAGGCAGAUGAGCAAGAGGGGGGCCAGUGUCAGGACGGCUGUGGCCACCAUUAAUGCCAGCGCAUUGAGGGAGAUGUCCCCACAGGCCAGUUUUAGCACUGCCAAGAUCUCAUAGAAGUAGUUGAUGACGUGGCCACAGAAGGGGAGGUGCCAGACAAGGAUGGACUGUAGCAGUGAGUUGGCAAAGCCUGUCCCCCAGCUCAGCGCUGCCAUCUGCAUGCAGGUCUGCCCACUCAUGAGCUCUGGGUACCUAAGCGGCUGGCAGAUAGCCACAUAACGGUCAUAUGCCAUCACAGCCAGCAGCAGGCACUCCGUUGAUCCCAGCGCCAGGGUCAGGUACAUCUGCAGGGCACAGCCAGGGAAGGAAAUGGUCCUCUGGGUUUCCAGGAAAUUGUCUAGCAUGAGAGGCACAAAGGAGGAGGUGCCGCAGAUGUCCAUGAGGGAGAGGUUGCUGAGAAGUACAUGGGGUUGUGCAGGCGAGGGUGCAGCACGUUCAGCCCUAUGAGGAGGGCGUUCCCCAACACAUUCACGGAGUAGAUGCCCAGGCAGAACACAAACAGGACCACCUCCAGGUUACAGUGCUCGUGUAGCCCCAUCAGGACGUAUUCCGUCACAGCUGUCUGGUUUGCCCACUUCAUCUCAUUCUCUCUCCUUUUCCAUCUGGACCACCCAGCUUUUUGGAAAAAGCUCCAACUGGCCUGGGAGCCCAGUGACCUGAUGUCUGAGCUGCAGCAGGUCAGCCUCCCUCUCUGGAAUUUAGUUUCACCAUCUGUAUAAUGAGGGAGUUGGACUUCAGAUCUGCAAUCUGGCCUUCUCAGCGCUGCAGUUCUGUGGACGUCACUGAGGGGAGGAUGGGGCACAUUCUAGUCCCCUAGGCUCCUCUCUGCUCUCCCCAGGAUGGGGUCAGAGGAGACAGCAGAGAAAGAUUCAUGUUUAAAAUGAUCGUUUGGAAUCCAAAGUGUUUUUGGUCAUUAACAGGAAGCAUCUUUUCUACAUUACGGUUUCAUGUGACCAAAUUAUGGCCAUAGUAUUUCAGAUUUAUUCAUCCACUAAGUAUUUAUUAAGUACCUAUUCUGUGCUAGGUAUCAGGUGCUGGGGCUAUAGCAGUAAGGAAAGUAAGUGGACAAAAGGAUUCCACACCUGUCACAGGCGCUGCCCCACUCCCUGAGUCAGGUGAGAUGAGCUCCGGAAGGCAGGUGGGUAAUGGAUGAUGCUCACCUAGUGUUCCUUGGGCCAUGAAGAUCAAAUAUUUCAGCCCCAUAGGAUGUGUAAGCUUGAUUUCUGGUCAUCUCUCCUUAAGGAAUCAUGGACCAUUCAUUAUUUUGUUUAAAAGGACACAUAAGAACGUACAUGUCUCAAUAGAGUUACUGGUCACAGGACUGAACUGUGGUCAUGAAAGCCAAGCAACUUACUUUCUGGCCUCCAUAUUGCUUUGUAGGAGAAAUGAUACUGACAAUGAUGUCACACGAGGAGGGAAGCCAGGCACGAAUCUGGUGGAGGUGCGGUCAGUUGUGACCAGCUUUGCAAAGGGAGCGGUGGGCGAGGCUGUGGUCUCUCCCAGGUGACCUCCAUCGCCAUGCAGAGCUGCUCUCACUUCUCCUCGGGAAAGGCCAGCGUCAGGUAUUCCUAGGAGGAAGCCCAGGUGUGUCCAGAGAACAGUAGUCUUGUUAGAACUGGAAAAAUGUCUUAUGGCCAGGUGGCCCCUGGUCUGAAGGAAAAAUAGGAGCUGAGUGUGAACUUUUAUCACUCAGAAGAUAUAAUCCACCUCUCCCCUCCUGCCCUUCGCUCCUGGGUUGGUUGUGAGGACAGUGCUUUGUGACAGCAGUGGAGCCCUGUCUGUCCUUCCGGGCUAGAUUUCUUCUUUCUCUUAUUCCUCCUGUUUCGUUGUAUCCACGAUUUGUCGAGUUGCAGGGCUCACCCUUUCCUGAAGAAACCAUCUCUUUUCCCAGCUCCGCACCUUUGUCCGAGAUGGAGGCGUGUCCUCCCGCCCAUCCCCAGUGGGGGGUGUUCUGCCCAUUCUCCAGAGCCCAGCACUGCUCCAUCUCUUUUCCUCCCUCUCCUUCCCCUUGCUGUUACCUGCUGCCUUCUUGUGCUCCCACUGCCCUUGGCCAUCCCUCUGUGUCAUUGUGCGCUGUGGUGCACCUGUCUUCUCUACUACACCUUAAGAGCAGGACUCUGCCUCCUUCCUACCAGCACCUCAUGCAGCAAGUGCUGCCAAUAGCAGGCACCCAGCAGAUAGCGAAUGCACGACUCCAAAACCCAGCUUUGCCUCCUGGCUGUAGUUCAGACUAGCUGUGUGACACUGACCAAGACACUUGACCUCUCUCAGACUCAGCUUCCUCCUUGAAGACUGGGAUGCUAUGUAGCUCAGAGGAAACAUACACCUGAAGGUGCUGCCCCGGGGGGUGCAAUGACCUGUUACUGAGGCUGGAUGGAGGAUGGCAUCCAUCAUCAGCUACAGGUGCCUCCUCUAUCUACAGGUUCCUGCUCCAUCUAUACUAGCCACCUCCUGGACAAGGGCUCCAGUGUCCUCCAUGACACCAGCUUUCUCCAGAGCCUGUGCAGGAUUUCCUUCCUCUACCCUGAAUCAGGGUGAUUCUUAAAGGACAGUUUCAGGAACAUAUAGGGGCACUUGGGUAAUCUUGGUCAGUAACUGACCUUUAACUAUCAUCCAUGUGAACAUCUACAGUUAGGGAUUUUCUUGGUGAUGUUUGGCAAAAAGUAAAGAAUUCCCCAAGUGUGAAGCCUCAUUCAUUCACUUAUUCAACAAAUAGUUAUUGAGCACCUACUAUGUGUUAGGCCCUGGGCCAGGUGCUGGGAAUACAGCAGAGACAGACCUGGCUCCUGCCCUCAUGGAGUUUGCAGUCAUUCAUUCACUCACUCGGUGACUUUGGACACCUCCCCCUCCUCUCUCCAGGCUUUAGAUCUCUGAGAUUCUCUCUGAGUCUGGGAUGUAAAGACAAAGUAAAACCUGAAAUCUGGAAAGCAGAACUAUAAGAGCUUUGUUUCUGAUGGGGGUGUUGCUGCAGACAGAACUAUGUCCAUCUCAAAUUCUGACACUGGACACAGGCGUGGGGGUUUCAAGCAGGCCAAGGGUGGGAAACCACCUGACUGCAUUUUUCUUUAUCACUCACACCUCUAACAGUAAGACCAAGUGGGCCUGGCGGAGGCAUUUGAGGGCUUUUGUGUGUGCAGGCUCUGGCCCGUCCUCCUGCCUUGCCUCCACCGCAUCCCUCAUGCACACCUGCUGCAGCCUCAUCAGACCACUCCCUGUCUUUUGGACAAAGCCUGUGUGCUCCAGUCCCAUCCCUCUUCUUGGGCAGUUUCUUCAGGCUGGAGUGCCUUUCUUUUCUACUCAUCCUUCAAGGCUCAGUUCACACACCACUGUCUCGUGCAGCCUUCUCUCAGAUGGCUUCAUAAAACUGACCACCCGGACAACAAGAUGGUCACACAGCUAUUAGUGGAGGUUAAGUUCAUUCUGCCUUCAUUAUAGUUCAUUUUUCUUGUAUAUCUCUCUCUGACUAGACUAUGAGCUAUUGCAGUGAAAGGGCUGUGUCCUUCAUCACUGUCACCCUCCAGUGACCCGCAGCCAGGAGGUGUCAGUGAUUGCCAUUUGAGUUGAACUAUUUAUUGACAUCCAGUGUUGUUCUGCCAAAAAUCCUGAUCCUAGGCAUGGUGGUUUGCACCUGUGGUCACAGCUACUCAGAAGGCUGAGGUGGGAGGAGUACUUGAGCCCAGGAGUUCGAGGUUACAGUGAACUAUGAUUGUGCCACUGCACUCCAGCCUGGGCAACAGAGUGAGGCCCUUUCUCUAAAAAAGCAAACGAAGAACGCUGAACCCAAGGUCUUGCCUCAAAAUCAAUUCCCCCUUCCCCCUCCAACACAUACACCGCAACAGAAUGAUACAGCUAUUGUGAUUGCUAGGAGAAGGGCUUUGGGCAGUGCCAGUCUCCUGUUUGCAGUAACACCUGCUCUUUCUGAAGAGCUACAUCAGUAACAUGGUGGGUUUUCCUCACAACUUAAAAGUCUGAUCGUAACACAUUCAUGGAAACUAGAACCAGCACACGAAACCAUUGGCUUGUGGCCCUAAAGAAAUAACUCUGUGUCCAGAAAAUGCCAUGUUACCAGGUUGCCUACAGCUUUGCCUGUAACAUGGGCACAGGCUGGGACAUCAGAUAGAAGCUGGUUCCCAUGGUGGCUGGGUUGGGAUGGGCUAAGUUAUGUUGCAGUAACGUACAACCUCAUCAUUUUAGUGGCUAGCAUGACGAAGUUUUAUUUCUCAUGCUACAUGUCUACUGUGGCUUUCCCGGUGGCUCAGGGUUCUCAGAGCCCCUGGCAGAUGGAGGCUCCACCCUGUGGGACGUCACCAGUUGUUAUGGCUGGGGAAGGACACACUGGAGGCUCUUGCUGCUCUGAGCCACAGGAGACAUUUGUCAUAUCUGCACACAGCCCACUGGCCCUGCGGCAUCCUACCACCUGCCCAGAAGGAGGAGAACCAGAAUUACUGCUGAGCAGCUCCUCUGCAUGUGGGUGCAAUGGCGUCUUAUGACUCUCAGAAAGCUACUCUAGUGGCCAUCUACCAGUGUCACGCAGUGUCACGCUCGGUCAUGGCCUGGAAGAUCAGAGUCACAGAGGGAUAGGACCUGGAGUGUCUCUGAAAAUAGCUGCCUGGUUUCACUCCCCGGUUUUACGCCUCUUGAGAAGCAGAGUGAUGCCUAGAAUGAGCCCUGGACUGGGAGGGCACGUCCCAGGUUUGAAUCGGGGCCUUUGUUCCUUUUCUGCUGUAUGACUUUGGUCAGAUUUCUCCUUCUGAGAAGUGGAGCCAAUUAAGCGAUCUCCGAUAUGCUGUAAUCUCUGAAACAUUUCCUCAUAUGUUUCUAGCAACUUCCAACCUGAGGUCUGAUAGACCCAGGGUUACUUUGCAAGCUAACUGACAUAUCAGUCUCAUUGUCUGGUAAAUCUAAUUUUAACCACUUAAUACUUAUUUUAGGCUUCACAAAUUAUUUUAAAAGAAAAGAUAGGGGCAUAACAAGAAGAAAGCUUCGGUUACAAUUUCCCCGAAAUGCCUGGAUCUGGGAUUCCUGCUUCCUGGCUGUGUGGCAGAGAAGAUGAGGAUGGCCCUGGAGUCAGACGGGACUAGGGUCCAAGCCCCAGCUCUUCCACUUGUUAACAAUGUUCUCAGCCUCAGCUUCCUUACCUAUACCAUGGAGACGGCAGUAUUUCCUUGUGGGCUUGUUUUAAGGAUCCAGUGACAGGAAGCAUGCGAAGCUCUUAGAACAGAGCCUGGCACUGGUAAAUAGUCAGUGAGCAGUAGAUGAUAUUAUUACCAUCCUGUCCCUAUCCCUGUCCCCCAGCAAAUAUUUUGGCUUUUAAAUGUUUUAAAUGAUUUCUUGAGAAUAAGCAAUGGGUCAGAUGAAAUCUCCUUACCUCUCACCUACUGGCCAUGGCCUAAAUGUCUGUAGGGAGCUGGAGCCAGGUGAGGGGAGCUGUGGUUUGGGAAGUGCCGAGUUCAUUAUGAGCAAGUGCACGGUGCUGGGAUGGGCUAGGUUCCCCGCACCUCGCCCUGCCACUGCCUCCCAGGACCUGCCUCUUGCUCCCCUGCCACAUAGACAGUCUGCUUGCCCCCUGCUUUCAGGGACCUCAUGGUCCCUGCCCAAUUUAAAGUUCAAACUCUGCAACUGCACAAAGUUGCAGGCUUGGCAGCUGUGGGACCUGGGCUUCAGAGACUCCAGGUUCCUCGGCCUGCCCCAGGAGGGCCCUGCUGAGGUGAAGUGGGCAUAGGAGAGAGAGUGGACAGAGAAUCUGAAUACUGGGUCACGUUGCAGUUCUGCGCCUUGGAUGCCAUAGGCUCCAGGCCCAUAAGCCCGGCUUCACUAGGCCUGGGUGUCUGGGUUGUGAAAUGGGGUGUCUCCUUCCAGGAUUGCCGUAAGGACCUGGAUUCAUCAAAGCUUAAAGUAAAUUGCUUUGUAAGGUGGGAGACACCGAGUACAGGCGAGGGACUUUAUUAGGUCAGGGAUUUAAUCAGGCAUCUGUUUUUACAGAUUUCUUUAUUCCUGUUCCCUCCCCUCCCCUUCCUGUCCUUUCACAAUAAAGAAUAACAACUUGACACAGCUUAGAGACUAAAAAUCAUCCUUCAAUAAAGCAGCAGAAGUUGCAAAGUUUCCUAUGAUGCUA